GGGGUUCCAGCGUCGACUCACGGAGUCCUUCGGAUGAGAGCGUCUGGGUGCCAGACGAGGCCGGGGGUUUGUUUUGGGUGGUUUGGGAGUCCGAGCUCGAGGGCUGGGCCAGGAAGGGCAGGCGAGGCGGGCGGCUCCGACGCGGGUCGCGAAGGCCCAGCCGCGUCCUCUGUCCCCAGGACGACUACAUUUCCCAGAGGCCAGCGGGGCGCGCGUACUCGAGUCUGCGGGGCGGAGGCCGCGGCUCGGGGCUGCUGGGCGUUCGGGGCGGCUUGGGGCGGCGGGACCACUGGAGUGAGCUGUGGGAGAGAUGGGGGUGUGCCUGUGUGUAAAAGAUCUGUCAGAGUGUGAGGCUCCGUGAGAGGGUGUGGUUUCUGUGUGUGUGUGUGUGUGUGUGUGACAGACCGAGAGUCCAGUGUGAGACCAGGGUAUGUUCGUGUGUGACAGAGCGAGACGGGCCAGUGUGAGAGACCAGUGAGUGUGAGAGAGAUAGGGAUGUGCCUGCAUUUGAAAGAGAGCGUGUGAAGCUCAGUGAGAGGUUGCGAGGUGUGUGGGUGUGUAAGUGUGUAACAGACCAGGUGUCCAGAGCGUGAGACCAGGAUGUAUUCGUGUGAGAGAGUGAGACGGGCUGGAUGGAGUGUGAGAGACCAGUGAGUGUGAGAGAUGGGCGUGUGCCUGUGUGUGAAAGGCCGGUCGGUCGGUGGGUGAGGCUCAAUGAGAGGCCGGUGUGUGUUCGAGAGAGAGAAGAAUCACCAUGUAUGCGAGACUAGACUGUGCAAGAACAGAGUGUGAGACUGUGGUAUGUUAAUGUGUGAAAGGGAGACCAGUGAGUGUGAGAAAUGGGUGUUUUGGGUGAAAGACCCGUCAGUGUGUGAGGCCGUGUUAUGUGUGUCUGACAGACUGAGAGAGACCAGAGUGUGAGACCAGGGUGUGUUCGUGUGUGAGAGACAACAUAGCGUGAGACCAGUGAGUGUGAGAGAGAUGAGCACGUGGCUGUGUGUGAAAGACCAGUCAUUAUGUGAGGCUCCUUGAGAGGCUGGUGUGUGUGUAUGAGAGAGAGAAAGAGACUAAACUGUGAGAGUCCAAAGAGUGAGACUAGGUUAUGUUGUUAUGAGUUUGUGAGAGAGAGGGAGGCGAUCAAAGUAUAGGACAAAGUUAUGUUUCCUGGCUUACGACUUCUAAGAUCCUUGGAAUCUCCAAAGUAUUAAGUGUCUUUUUGCAUGCUAAUGAUUGGUGGGCUGGCAGCCUGUAGGUUGAUCACGGUAAGGGAUGGUCACAAGAACAAUCUAGGCAGGAUUAGAGGGUUGGGAUUACCUGCCCCAUCCCUCAAUCUCCAGGGAAAGGAAAGGGAGCCACAGGUUAAACUGAUCAUCAGUGGUCAGUGAUUUAACCAGUCAUGCCUACAUUAUGAAGCUUCCAUAAAAACCCAAAAGGACUGGGUUCAUCAAACUUCCAGAUAGCUGAACACUGGAGGUUCCUGUAGGAUGAGCCCCUUCCUAUAUAACCUUGUCCUAUGCAUUUCUUCACCUGCAUCCUUUGUAAUAUCCUUUAUUACUACAAACGUGUUUCCCUAAGUUCUGUGAGCUGCCCUAGCAAAUUAAUUGAACGCAAGGAGGGGGUCAUAGGAACCCCGAUUUAUAGCUAGUCAGAAGCACAAGUAAAACAACCUGGGGUUUGCAACUGGCAUUGGAAGUGGGGAGCAAUUUUGUAGGGCUGAGCCCUCAACCUGUGGGAUCUUAUGCUGUCUCCAGGUAGAUAGUGUCAGAAUUGGGUUGCCCUAGAGGUCACCCACCUGGUAUUCACUGGGUUGCCCUAGAGGUCACCCACCUGGUAUUCACUGAAGAACUUAUUGCUUGCCUGGUGUGUGUGUGUGUGUGUGUGUGUGUGUGUGUGUGUGUGUAGAUCCCCACACAUCUGGUCUUAGAACUGUUUUGUGUUGUGUGAGUGGAGUAGGAGAAACAGUUUGUUUUUCCUCUUUGUCACCUGAGUGUGUUAUCAGGGACUGGAUUGUGAGAAUCCAGAGUGUGAGACCAGGGUAUAUCAAUGUGUGAGAGAAAUAGAUGUGCCUGUGUGAAAGAUGAACAAGUAUGAGGCUCCCUGGAGUCUGAGAAAGAUCAUGUGUGUGUCUGAGUAAAAGCAAGAGACUAGACUGAGAGUUCAGUGAUUGGGAGAGACUGGGGUAUGUUGGUGUGAGUGUGUGAGAGACCAAUGGGUAUGUGAGAGACUAGAGUAUGUCUCUGUCUGGACUGGUAGGUUGUGAGAGGGUGUAUCACAGUAUGAAAAAGAUUGGAGUGAGAGUGACCAGUAUGUAUUUUGUGUGCAUGAGAUAAAGCAGUUGGAAUAUGAGAGAUCAGAGUGUGUUUGUGUAUCUGUGUGAGACACUGGAGCAUUUGAGUAACUGAGGCCUCUUUGAAAGAUACCAUUGAAUGUGUAUGUAUGAGAGACCAUCAUGUUUAUAUGUGUGAAAGAGGGAGAGAAAGACUAGUGAUGUGGUUGUGUGAGAGACCAAAAUGGGUGAGAAAGAAACUAUGUGAACCAUGGUGUGUUAUCCAAAAGGCUUUACAAAUAUAACCUCUGUGAGGUUGUGAAGCAUGCAUGUGUGAGUGAGACAGAGAUAAGGGACAGUGAGCUGUGUGUGUGAGAGAAGUAAGAUUGGGGGUAUGUGUGAAGGUGUUGGUGAAUCACCACGUGUGCUUAUAUUCAUGUCCUCAGGCAAUGGAAAUGUGACUGUGUAUAUGUGCUUGUUUUGGGGUGCUUGUGAUUGUGUCCUCCGUGUGACCAUGAAACCUGUGUUAGUGUUUGUAUGUCACCCUGUAUACCCAUAAUUGUGGCCCUGUAUGACUGCUGUGUAUGGAGAGACUACUUGGAAGAUUGAUAGGAUUGGAUUCUUUAUGAGUGUGGCUGUUUGGAAUUGUGUGUUGCCGGGAUAGGAAAUGUGGAAUAGAAUUCCUGUCCCCAGUCCAAGGGUUUCAGUAAGAAGCAAAGCUGGGGUGACUGAAGCUCCUAACUGAAGCAGGAGACACCCUCACUUCUGUGUGACAGGAGGGUAAUUAAGGGGCUGGGACAGAGGUGAGAGUGAAAGUGGCAGAAUUGAGUGCUAAAGGUUCCAUCGUUUCAGGCCUUGCCCUCCCAAGACACUGUUCUUCAAGAGAAAGACCAGAAGAGAAGGCAAAAAUGAAUGUUGAAGUAGUAAAAGUCAUGCCCCAGGACUUAGUGACAUUCAAGGAUGUGGCAAUAGAUUUUUCCCAGGAAGAAUGGCAAUGGAUGAACCCUGCUCAGAAGCGUUUAUACAGGAGUAUGAUGUUGGAGAACUAUCAGAGCCUGGUAUCACUUGGUCUUUGCAUUUCUAAGCCAUAUGUGAUCUCCUUAUUGGAGCAAGGGAGAGAGCCUUGGGAGAUGACGAGUGAGAUGACAAGAAGCCCAUUCUCAGAUUGGGAAUCUAUAUAUGUGACACAGGAAUUACCUCUGAAGCAGUUCAUGUAUGAUGAUGCAUGCAUGGAGGGAAUUACUAGCUAUGGACUUGAGUGUUCCACUUUUGAAGAAAAUUGGAAAUGGGAAGACCUUUUUGAGAAGCAGAUGGGAAGUCAUGAGAUGUUUAGCAAGAAAGAAAUAAUCACUCAUAAAGAAACCAUCACUAAGGAAACAGAAUUCAAAUAUACUAAAUUUGGGAAAUGUAUCCAUCUGGAAAACAUAGAAGAGAGUAUUUAUAAUCACACAUCAGAUAAAAAAAGCUUCUCCAAAAAUUCUAUGGUAAUAAAACACAAGAAAGUCUAUGUAGGAAAGAAGCUUUUUAAAUGUAAUGAAUGUGACAAAACCUUCACCCAUAGCUCAUCCCUUACUGUUCAUUUUAGAAUUCAUACUGGUGAAAAACCAUAUGCAUGUGAGGAAUGUGGAAAAGCCUUCAAGCAAAGGCAACACCUUGCUCAACAUCACAGAACACAUACUGGAGAGAAACUCUUUGAAUGUAAAGAAUGUAGGAAAGCCUUCAAACAAAGUGAACACCUUAUUCAGCAUCAAAGAAUUCAUACUGGAGAAAAACCAUAUAAAUGUAAGGAAUGCAGAAAAGCCUUCAGACAGCCUGCACACCUUGCUCAGCAUCAGAGAAUUCAUACUGGAGAGAAACCCUAUGAAUGUAAAGAAUGUGGCAAAGCCUUCAGUGAUGGCUCGUCUUUUGCUCGACAUCAGAGAUGUCACACUGGCAAAAGACCCUAUGAAUGUAUUGAGUGUGGGAAGGCUUUUAGGUAUAACACAUCUUUUAUUCGUCACUGGAGGAGUUAUCAUACUGGAGAGAAGCCUUUUAAUUGCAUUGAUUGUGGGAAAGCCUUCAGUGUUCACAUAGGACUUAUUCUGCAUAGGAGAAUUCAUACAGGAGAGAAACCUUACAAAUGUGGUGUGUGUGGAAAAACCUUCAGCUCGGGUUCAUCCCGUACUGUACAUCAGAGAAUUCAUACAGGAGAGAAACCUUAUGAAUGUGAUAUAUGUGGGAAAGAUUUUAGCCAUCAUGCAUCACUCACUCAGCAUCAAAGAGUACAUUCUGGAGAGAAACCGUAUGAAUGCAAGGAAUGUGGGAAAGCCUUUAGGCAGAAUGUACACCUUGUUAGUCAUUUGAGAAUUCAUACUGGUGAAAAACCCUAUGAAUGUAAAGAAUGUGGAAAAGCUUUUAGAAUCAGUUCACAGCUGGCUACUCAUCAGAGAAUUCAUACUGGAGAGAAGCCUUAUGAAUGUAUUGAAUGUGGAAAUGCUUUCAAACAGAGAUCACACCUUGCCCAACAUCAGAAAACUCAUACAGGAGAGAAACCUUAUGAGUGUAAUGAAUGCGGGAAAGCCUUCAGCCAAACUUCCAAUCUUACUCAACAUCAAAGAAUUCAUACUGGAGAGAAACCCUAUAAAUGUACUGAAUGUGGAAAGGCUUUUAGUGAUAGCUCAUCCUGUGCUCAGCAUCAAAGACUCCACACUGGCCAAAGGCCCUAUCAGUGUUUUGAAUGUGGGAAGGCGUUCAGAAGAAAGUUAUCCUUAAUUUGUCAUCAAAGAAGUCAUACUGGAGAAGAACCUUAAGAAUGUAGUGCAUGUGGCCAAGCCUUUAGUUAUCACCAAUCCCCUACUGUUAAUCAGAGAUGUCCCACUGGAUAAAAAACAUAUAAAUGUAAGAAAUGUAGAAAAACCUUCAGCCAGGAGGCUGGCAAGAUGGCCGAAUAGGAACAGCUCUGAUCUGCAGUUCCCAGUGAGAUCAACGCAGAAGGUGGGUGCUUUCUGUAUUUCCAGCUGAGGUACCUGGCUCAUCUCAUUGGGACUGGUUAGACAGUGGGUGCAGCCCACGGAGGGUGAGCUGAAGCAGGGUGGGGCGUAACCUCACCUGGGAAGUGCAAGGAGUCGGGGAUCUCCCUCCCCUAGCCAAGGGAAGCCAUGAGGGACUGUGCCAUGAGGAAUGGUGCACUCCGGCACAGAUACUACGCUUUUCCCAUGGUCUUCGCAACCCACAGACCAGGAGAUCCCCCUUGGGUGCCUAUGCCACCAAGGCCCUGGGUUUCAAGCACAAAACUGGGCGGCCAUUCGGGCAGACACCGAGCUAGCUGUAGGAGUUUUUUUGAUAGCCCAGUGGCACCUGGAAUGCCAGUGAAACAGAACCGCUUACUCCCUUGUUAAGGGGGCUGAAGCCGGGGAGCCAAGUGGUUCCCAUGCCCACUGAGCCCAGCAAGCUAAGAUCCACUGGCUUGGAAUUCUCCCUGCCAGCACAGCAGUCUGAAGUCAACCUGGGAUGAUCAAGCUUGGUGGGGGGAGGGGCGCCAACCAUUACCAAAGCUUGAAUAGGUGGUUUUCCCCUCACAGCGUAAACAAAGCCAUGGGGAAGUUCCAGCUGAGCAGAGCCCUCCACAGCUCAGCAAAGCCUCUGUAGCCAGACUGCCUCUCUAGAUUCCUCCUCUCUGGGCAGCGCAUCUUUGAAAAAAGUGCAGAUAAAACCCUCAUCUCCCUGGGACAAAGCACGUGGGGGAAAGGGGUGGCUGUGGGCACAGCUUCAGCAGACUUAAACAUUCCUGCCUGCCAGCUCUGAAGAGAGCAGCAGUUCUUCCAGCACAGCGCUUGAGCUCUGCUAAGGGACAGACUGCCUCCUCAAGUGGGUCCCUGACCCCCAUGCCUCCUGACGGGGAGACACCUCCCAGCAGGGGUCCACAGACACCUCAUACAGGAGAGCUCUGGCUGGCAUCUGGUGGGUGCCCCUCUGGGACAAAGCUUCCAGAGGAAGGAACAGGCAGCAAUCUUUGCUGUUCUGCAGCCUCCACCGGUGAUACCCAGGCAGAUAUGGUCUGGAGUGGACCUCCAGCAAACUCCAGCAGACCUGCAGCCGAGGGGCCUCACUGUUAGAAGGAAAACUAACAGGAAUAUAAUCAACAUCAACAAAGGACAUCCACACAGAAACCCCAUCUGAAGGUUACCAGCAUCAAAGACCAAAGGUAGAUAAAUUCACGAAGAUGAGGAGAAACCAGUGCAAAAAGCCUGAAAAUUCCAAAAACCAGAAUGCCUCUUCUCCUCCAAAGGAUCACAACUCCUUGCCGGCAAGGGAACAAAACUGGAUAGAGAAUGAGUUUGACAAAUUGACAGAAGUAGGCUUCAGAAGGUGGGAAAUAACAAACUCCUCUGAGCUAAAGGAGCAUGUUCUAACCCAAUGCAAGGAAGCUAAGAACCUUGAAAAAAGGUUAGAGGAAUUGCUAACUAGAAUAACCAGUUUAGAGAAGAACAUAAAUGACCUGAUGGAGCUGAAAAACACAGCAUGAGAACUUCGUGAAGCAUACAGAAGAAAAACCUUCAGCCAGAUUGAAUGCUUUACAGGGAAGAAUUCAUACUGCAGAGCGGUCUUAACAAUGUAAAGAAUGUGCAAAUGUCCUCAGACAAGAUGCACACCUUGCUCAUUAGUGAGUUCAUUUCAGGCAGCCAGCUCUUCCUCACCCACUACAUCACCAAGUCCUGUGGAUAUAUCUGCUAAAUAUUUUUGGAAUUUAUCCACUUCUUUUGGUUCCCCAGUCCAAAACACAGUCAUUUCACCUGGACUAUUUCAAUCAUUACACAGGUGUCCAACCUUUUGUCUUCCCUGGGCCACAUUGGAAGAAGAAAAAUUGUCUUGUGCCACACAUACAAUACACUAACAUUAACAAUAGCUGAUGAGCUAAGAAAAAAAAAAAGUCUGUGCAUAGUUUUAGUGAUACACCACCUCCGAUAAGCAAAAAAGUCCUCACAUUCAAUGGGUUGCAUACCCAUGAAUUCUAAAACUUCAUCCUCUUUUGUCCCUUUCGAGUUAACAUUACAGCCACAGUGACCUUUCAAAAAUGCAAAUUAAGUUACUCUUAAAACUCUAGUUAAAAUACUUGAUGUACAUAAAGUGCUUAGCAAAAUGACCAACUCAUACUAAGUGCUUAGUAAAUGUUAGAUAAGUAUUCUCCAGAAUUGAUGUAAAUUAUUUUUAAACAGUGCAUUCUUGAAAGCAGUAUGGCAGUCAUAAAAAUUUUGGAACCAAAACAGUAUCUUUUUUUAAGCUAAAAAAAAAGUUUUAAAUGGUGUCUUUCUAUGUUGCCCAGGGUGGUCUCAAACUCCUGUGCUCAAGUGACCCUCCCACCUCAUUCUCAAGUGGCUGCAAUUACAGGCAACCAGCCUGACUUAAAACAGUAUCUUAAGGUAGAUGGUGAUUAGCACAUGUAGUAUGCUUAACAUUUAAUAUUAUAAUAAGACAUCACAGCGGCUGUCUCAUGAUUAAGGCUGUGUUCCCUUGUUGGUGAGGAAAUUAAUUAUGACUUGAUAAAUAGAACAUGUUUUAAGAAGUGGCUAUAUAGCUCUGGAUAAAACGAACAAAAGAAUUAGAAUUCCUGCGGGGAAUAUAUACAAGACUUUAUUUAGUCAAGUAAAAAAAAAUCACUAAUGUUUAACUGAAGAAAGAGAAAUUGAAUAAUAUAGUUCUAUUUCAACAUGUGGGUUCACAGAUUUAUUCUAACCUUCCAAGUAAAGUUGUUCCACUAGUAAAGUUGUUCUGGAGUAUAUUUUUUUUAAAAAAAACACUUAAAAUGUUCCACUUCUUUCAUGAGGCUAAGUCAACUCUGAUAUCAAACCAAGGGGAAAGAAAUGAAAUUAUAGGUGAGUUUACUUAGUUAUAUACAAAAGGAAAUUAUUAGCCUCUGCUGAUGGAGAACAGAGGCUGUGAAUAAAUGGAGAUCCAUAACAUGAUCCUACAUGAAUGUUUCAAUAUUGUAAUCCUGUAAGUUACUUUUACAUUGACAGUUCUGAAAUUCAUGUUGAGUGUUAAUUAGGCAGGAAUCAGAAGGGAGGUUUUGUAGAAGGUCGUAUCCAUGGGUUUUUUAUAUUUGAAAAGUGUUUUCGAUGUAUCAUUGGGGGAGAUUAAAUGUCUUUGACAGUUGUCCAACUAGAAAUAAAGUCAGCAUCCCAUUUGACUCCUUACACAGAAGUUCAUUCUAUACUCAUUACAGAUGUAAGAGGUUAAGAUGGUAGAGGAGAAUGUAGAGUAUUUCUGUGCCUUUAGGUUCAGGAGGUCUUUGAUAAGCAGGACAAGGUCCAGAAGCCAUGAAGAGAGAAUGACAGGACUGUGUAGAAGAUUUAAACCUUUUUCAUGGCGUAAGAUACUGUAUGCAAAGUUAAAAGGCAUAUGACAGGCUGAGAGAUAUCUUAAACAUACAUUAGAAAGGAUAUAGCCCUUGAAAAAGGGCUGUUGGAAAGCAGCAAGGAUAAGGUGCACAGUCUUGCAGAGCAUGUCAACAAAAUUUAUUGGAUGAAGAAAUUAAAAUGGUUAAAUAGAAGAAGUUCUCAACCUCACUAAUGAUCAGAUAAGUGCAGAUUGUAAAAGUCCUCAUCCCCACCAACACAAACCAGCAGAAAUUUUAUGUGAAUGUGAAGUUUGGAUAAUAUCCAGUAUUGUCGCAGGUGUGAGAAACCGUAUUUUCAAAUAUUGAGAGGGUAAAUUAGAGGAAAGCCAUUUUAGAGGGCAAUGUGGUGUUACCUGUCAGCAUUUUGAAUAUAAUUACCCUUUGCCACAAUUCUACACCUAGUCAGUUAUGUUCUCAAAAAGCACAAGUGCAGAAAUAUAGAUGCAUAAGCAAAUGUGUUGCAGAAUUGUGAAAAAUUUGGAAAAAAUGUUUAGUGCUAUUAAAGUUAUGGGUUACUUAAGUUACAGAAAAUCAGUUUAGUAGAUCACUGUGUAGUUACGGAAAAUGAGAUGGAUCUCUACUCAAAGAUGUCUUGCAGUUUAUGAACUGAGAUGUAACUUCAUGACUAACAUGAUGACAUCGUUAUUAACUACAUAAACUUUAUAAAGCUUAAAAAA